AAGUCGCGACCAGAGCCAUUGGAGGGCGCGGGGACUGCAACCCUAAUCAGAGCCCAAAUGGCGCAGUGGGAAAUGCUGCAGAAUCUUGACAGCCCCUUUCAGGAUCAGCUGCACCAGCUUUACUCGCACAGCCUCCUGCCUGUGGACAUUCGACAGUACUUGGCUGUCUGGAUUGAAGACCAGAACUGGCAGGAAGCUGCACUUGGGAGUGAUGAUUCCAAGGCUACCAUGCUAUUCUUCCACUUCUUGGAUCAGCUGAACUAUGAGUGUGGCCGUUGCAGCCAGGACCCAGAGUCCUUGUUGCUGCAGCACAAUUUGCGGAAAUUCUGCCGGGACAUUCAGCCCUUUUCCCAGGAUCCUACCCAGUUGGCUGAGAUGAUCUUUAACCUCCUUCUGGAAGAAAAAAGAAUUUUGAUCCAGGCUCAGAGGGCCCAAUUGGAACAAGGAGAGCCAGUUCUCGAAACACCUGUGGAGAGCCAGCAACAUGAGAUUGAAUCCCGGAUCCUGGAUUUAAGGGCUAUGAUGGAGAAGCUGGUAAAAUCCAUCAGCCAACUGAAAGACCAGCAGGAUGUCUUCUGCUUCCGAUAUAAGAUCCAGGCCAAAGGGAAGACACCCUCUCUGGACCCCCAUCAGACCAAAGAGCAGAAGAUUCUGCAGGAAACUCUCAAUGAACUGGACAAAAGGAGAAAGGAGGUGCUGGAUGCCUCCAAAGCACUGCUAGGCCGAUUAACUACCCUAAUCGAGCUACUGCUGCCAAAGUUGGAGGAGUGGAAGGCCCAGCAGCAAAAAGCCUGCAUCAGAGCUCCCAUUGACCACGGGUUGGAACAGCUGGAGACAUGGUUCACAGCUGGAGCAAAGCUGUUGUUUCACCUGAGGCAGCUGCUGAAGGAGCUGAAGGGACUGAGUUGCCUGGUUAGCUAUCAGGAUGACCCUCUGACCAAAGGGGUGGACCUACGCAACGCCCAGGUCACAGAGUUGCUACAGCGUCUGCUCCACAGAGCCUUUGUGGUAGAAACCCAGCCCUGCAUGCCCCAAACUCCCCAUCGACCCCUCAUCCUCAAGACUGGCAGCAAGUUCACCGUCCGAACAAGGCUGCUGGUGAGACUCCAGGAAGGCAAUGAGUCACUGACUGUGGAAGUCUCCAUUGACAGGAAUCCUCCUCAAUUACAAGGCUUCCGGAAGUUCAACAUUCUGACUUCAAACCAGAAAACUUUGACCCCCGAGAAGGGGCAGAGUCAGGGUUUGAUUUGGGACUUUGGUUACCUGACUCUGGUGGAGCAACGUUCAGGUGGUUCAGGAAAGGGCAGCAAUAAGGGGCCACUAGGUGUGACAGAGGAACUGCACAUCAUCAGCUUCACGGUCAAAUAUACCUACCAGGGUCUGAAGCAGGAGCUGAAAACGGACACCCUCCCUGUGGUGAUUAUUUCCAACAUGAACCAGCUCUCAAUUGCCUGGGCUUCAGUUCUCUGGUUCAAUUUGCUCAGCCCAAACCUUCAGCCUACACUGCUCCCACCCCUGCAGAACCAGCAGUUCUUCUCCAACCCCCCCAAGGCCCCCUGGAGCUUGCUGGGCCCUGCUCUCAGUUGGCAGUUCUCCUCCUAUGUUGGCCGAGGCCUCAACUCAGACCAGCUGAGCAUGCUGAGAAACAAGCUGUUCGGGCAGAACUGUAGGACUGAGGAUCCAUUAUUGUCCUGGGCUGACUUCACUAAGCGAGAGAGCCCUCCUGGCAAGUUACCAUUCUGGACAUGGCUGGACAAAAUUCUGGAGUUGGUACAUGACCACCUGAAGGAUCUCUGGAAUGAUGGACGCAUCAUGGGCUUUGUGAGUCGGAGCCAGGAGCGCCGGCUGCUGAAGAAGACCAUGUCUGGCACCUUUCUACUGCGCUUCAGUGAAUCGUCAGAAGGGGGCAUUACCUGCUCCUGGGUGGAGCACCAGGAUGAUGACAAGGUGCUCAUCUACUCUGUGCAACCGUACACGAAGGAGGUGCUGCAGUCACUCCCGCUGACUGAAAUCAUCCGCCAUUACCAGUUGCUCACUGAGGAGAAUAUACCUGAAAACCCACUGCGCUUCCUCUAUCCCCGAAUCCCCCGGGAUGAAGCUUUUGGGUGCUACUACCAGGAGAAAGUUAAUCUCCAGGAACGGAGGAAAUACCUGAAACACAGGCUCAUUGUGGUCUCUAAUAGACAGGUGGAUGAACUGCAACAACCGCUGGAGCUUAAGCCAGAGCCAGAGCUGGAGUCAUUAGAGCUGGAACUAGGGCUGGUGCCAGAGCCAGAGCUCAGCCUGGACUUAGAGCCACUGCUGAAGGCAGGGCUGGAUCUGGGGCCAGAGCUAGAGUCUGUGCUGGAGUCCACUCUGGAGCCUGUGAUAGAGCCCACACUAUGCAUGGUAUCACAAACAGUGCCAGAGCCAGACCAAGGACCUGUAUCACAGCCAGUGCCAGAGCCAGAUUUGCCCUGUGAUCUGAGACAUUUGAACACUGAGCCAAUGGAAAUCUUCAGAAACUGUGUAAAGAUUGAAGAAAUCAUGCCGAAUGGUGACCCACUGUUGGCUGGCCAGAACACCGUGGAUGAGGUUUACGUCUCCCGCCCCAGCCACUUCUACACUGAUGGACCCUUGAUGCCUUCUGACUUCUAGGAACCACAUUUCCUCUGUUCUUUUCAUAUCUCUUGCCCUUCCUACUCCUCAUAGCAUGAUAUUGUUCUCCAAGGAUGGGAAUCAGGCAUGUGUCCCUUCCAAGCUGUGUUAACUGUUCAAACUCAGGCCUGUGUGACUCCAUUGGGGUGAGAGGUGAAAGCAUAACAUGGGUACAGAGGGGACAACAAUGAAUCAGAACAGAUGCUGAGCCAUAGGUCUAAAUAGGAUCCUGGAGGCUGCCUGCUGUGCUGGGAGGUAUAGGGGUCCUGGGGGCAGGCCAGGGCAGUUGACAGGUACUUGGAGGGCUCAGGGCAGUGGCUUCUUUCCAGUAUGGAAGGAUUUCAACAUUUUAAUAGUUGGUUAGGCUAAACUGGUGCAUACUGGCAUUGGCCCUUGGUGGGGAGCACAGACACAGGAUAGGACUCCAUUUCUUUCUUCCAUUCCUUCAUGUCUAGGAUAACUUGCUUUCUUCUUUCCUUUACUCCUGGCUCAAGCCCUGAAUUUCUUCUUUUCCUGCAGGGGUUGAGAGCUUUCUGCCUUAGCCUACCAUGUGAAACUCUACCCUGAAGAAAGGGAUGGAUAGGAAGUAGACCUCUUUUUCUUACCAGUCUCCUCCCCUACUCUGCCCCUAAGCUGGCUGUACCUGUUCCUCCCCCAUAAAAUGAUCCUGCCAAUCUAAUGUGAGUGUGAAGCUUUGCACACUAGUUUAUGCUACCUAGUCUCCACUUUCUCAAUGCUUAGGAGACAGAUCACUCCUGGAGGCUGGGGAUGGUAGGAUUGCUGGGGAUUUUUUUUUUUUUAAACAGGGUCUCACUCUGUUGCCCAGGCUAGAGUGCAAUGGUGCAAUCACAGCUCACUGCAGCCUCAACCUCCUGGGUUCAAGCAAUCCUCCUACCUCAGCCUCCUGGGUAGCUAGCACCAUGGCAUGCGCCACCAUGCCCUAUUUUUUUUUUUUAAAGACAGGGUCUUGCUAUAUUGCCCAGGCUGGUCUUGAACUGGGCUCAAGUGAUCCUCACGCCUUGGCCUCCCAAAGUGCUGGGAUUAUAGGCAUGAGCCACUGUGCUUGGCCAGGAUUUUUUUUUUUUUUUUUUUGAGAUGGAGUUUCUCUCUUGUUGUCCAGGCUGGAGUGCAAUGGUGUGAUCUCGGCUCACUGCAACCUCCGCCUUCCGGGUUCAAGUGACUCUCCUGCCUCAGCCUCCCCAGUAGCUGGGAUUACAGAUCUGCACCACCAUGCCCAGCUAAUUUUGUAUUUUUAGUAGAGACGGGGUUUCUCCAUGUUGGUCAGGCUGGUCUCGAACUCCUGACCUCAAGUGAUCUGUCCACCUCGGCCUCCCAGAGUGCUGGGAUUACAGGCGUGAGCCACUGUUCCCAGCAGGAAUUUCUUUUUUAUAGUAUUGGAUAAAGUUUGGUGUUUUUACAGAGGAGAAGCAAUGGGUCUUAGCUCUUUCUCUAUUAUGUUAUCAUCCUCCCUUUUUUGUACAAUAUGUUGUUUACCUGAAAGGAAGGUUUCUAUUCGUUGGUUGUGGACCUGGACAAAGUCCAAGUCUGUGGAACUUAAAACCUUGAAGGUCUGUCAUAGGACUCUGGACAAUCUCACACCUUAGCUAUUCCCAGGGAACCCCAGGGGGCAACUGACAUUGCUCCAAGAUGUUCUCCUGAUGUAGCUUGAGAUAUAAAGGAAAGGCCCUGCACAGGUGGCUGUUUCUUGUCUGUUAUGUCAGAGGAACAGUCCUGUUCAGAAAGGGGCUCUUCUGAGCAGAAAUGGCUAAUAAACUUUGUGCUGAUCUGGAAA